GAGGCGGAAGCGCCCGCAGCCCGGUACCGGCUCCUCCUGGGCUCCCUCUAGCGCCUUCCCCCCGGCCCGACUCCGCUGGUCAGCGCCAAGUGACUUACGCCCCCGACCCUGAGCCCGGACCGCUAGGCGAGGAGGAUCAGAUCUCCGCUCGAGAAUCUGAAGGUGCCCUGGUCCUGGAGGAGUUCCGUCCCAGCCCGCGGUCUCCCGGUACUGUCGGGCCCCGGCCCUCUGGAGCUUCAGGAGGCGGCCGUCAGGGUCGGGGAGUAUUUGGGUCCGGGGUCUCAGGGAAGGGCGGCGCCUGGGUCUGCGGUAUCGGAAAGAGCCUGCUGGAGCCAAGUAGCCCUCCCUCUCUUGGGACAGACCCCUCGGUCCCAUGUCCAUGGGGGCACCGCGGUCCCUCCUCCUGGCCCUGGCUGCUGGCCUGGCCGUUGCCCGUCCGCCCAACAUCGUGCUGAUCUUUGCCGACGACCUCGGCUAUGGGGACCUGGGCUGCUAUGGGCACCCCAGCUCUACCACUCCCAACCUGGACCAGCUGGCGGCGGGAGGGCUGCGGUUCACAGACUUCUACGUGCCUGUGUCUCUGUGCACACCCUCUAGGGCCGCCCUCCUGACCGGCCGGCUCCCGGUUCGGAUGGGCAUGUACCCUGGCGUCCUGGUGCCCAGCUCCCGGGGGGGCCUGCCCCUGGAGGAGGUGACCGUGGCCGAAGUCCUGGCUGCCCGAGGCUACCUCACAGGAAUGGCCGGCAAGUGGCACCUUGGGGUGGGGCCUGAGGGGGCCUUCCUGCCCCCCCAUCAGGGCUUCCAUCGAUUUCUAGGCAUCCCGUACUCCCACGACCAGGGCCCCUGCCAGAACCUGACCUGCUUCCCGCCGGCCACUCCUUGCGACGGUGGCUGUGACCAGGGCCUGGUCCCCAUCCCACUGUUGGCCAACCUGUCCGUGGAGGCGCAGCCCCCCUGGCUGCCCGGACUAGAGGCCCGCUACAUGGCUUUCGCCCAUGACCUCAUGGCCGACGCCCAGCGCCAGGAUCGCCCCUUCUUCCUGUACUAUGCCUCUCACCACACCCACUACCCUCAGUUCAGUGGGCAGAGCUUUGCAGAGCGUUCAGGCCGCGGGCCAUUUGGGGACUCCCUGAUGGAGCUGGAUGCAGCUGUGGGGACCCUGAUGACAGCCAUAGGGGACCUGGGGCUGCUUGAAGAGACGCUGGUCAUCUUCACUGCAGACAAUGGACCUGAGACCAUGCGUAUGUCCCGAGGCGGCUGCUCCGGUCUCUUGCGGUGUGGAAAGGGAACGACCUACGAGGGCGGUGUCCGAGAGCCUGCCUUGGCCUUCUGGCCAGGUCAUAUCGCUCCCGGCGUGACCCACGAGCUGGCCAGCUCCCUGGACCUGCUGCCUACCCUGGCAGCCCUGGCUGGGGCCCCACUGCCCAAUGUCACCUUGGAUGGCUUUGACCUCAGCCCCCUGCUGCUGGGCACAGGCAAGAGCCCUCGGCAGUCUCUCUUCUUCUACCCGUCCUACCCAGACGAGGUCCGUGGGGUUUUUGCUGUGCGGACUGGAAAGUACAAGGCUCACUUCUUCACCCAGGGCUCUGCCCACAGUGAUACCACUGCAGACCCUGCCUGCCACGCCUCCAGCUCUCUGACUGCUCAUGAGCCCCCGCUGCUCUAUGACCUGUCCAAGGACCCUGGUGAGAACUACAACCUGCUGGGGGGUGUGGCCGGGGCCACCCCAGAGGUGCUGCAAGCCCUGAAACAGCUUCAGCUGCUCAAGGCCCAGUUAGACGCAGCUGUGACCUUCGGCCCCAGCCAGGUGGCCCGGGGCGAGGACCCCGCCCUGCAGAUCUGCUGUCAUCCUGGCUGCACCCCCCGCCCAGCUUGCUGCCAUUGCCCAGAUCCCCAUGCCUGAGGGCCCCUCGGCUGGCCUGGGCAUGUGAUGGCUCCUCACUGGGAGCCUGUGGGGGAGGCUCAGGUGUCUGGAGGGGGUUUGUGCCUGAUAACGUAAUAACACCAGUGGAGACUUGCAGAUGUGACAAUUCGUCCAAUCCUGGGGUAAUGCUGUGUGCUGGUGCCGGUCCCCUGUGGUACGAAUGAGGAAACUGAGGUGCAGAGAGGUUCAGGACUUGUACAAGAUCACCCAGCCAGAAAGAGGUUGGGCUGGGAUUUGAACCCUGGUGUCGUGGCUCUGGAAGCUGCCCUGGCGCCUUGGUGAUCUGCGUGGGUCAGUGCACACAGGCACACGUCAGCCUCAAGGACAUGGGCACAUCUGUUCACAGGAGCAGCGCCACGUGCCUUUGAGUGCCAGGAACGGGGUGGGAGGGUGGGAGGGUGUGAGGGCCAGAAGACUCAGAAGAUGCAAAGUGCCUGAGAGAGACGGGAUAUUCCCCCAGAAGAAGCAUUCUUAGAGACACAGGCACUGGACCUCCUUGGUUCUUAUAAGAAACCUGUCUGAAGCUGGGUGAUGAGUUGCACACUCCAGGUGGGGCUAAGGGGCCUGGAGCCCCUGCUGGCUCCUAGGAAGGCACAGCAGCAGGCCCUGAGACGGCUCCUCUGGGGCCCCUCCACCCUCCCAGGCCUCUGCAUUUCACCUGUGCCCACACUUCUGUCUCCUGCCUUCACCUUUUGACCCACUACUAACGAUUCUCCACCCAGCAGACAAAGUGAUCUCUUAAAAAUAUCUGUUGGCUGGGCACGGUGGCUCACGCCUGUAAUCCCAGCACUUUAGGAAGCCGAGGCGGGUGGAUCACCUGAGGUCGGGAGUUCGAGACCAGCCUGACCAACAUGGAGAAACCCCAUCUCUACUAAAAAUACAAAAUUAGCCAGGUGUAGUGGUGCAUCCCUGUAAUCCCAGCUACUUGGGAGUCUGAGGCUGGAGAAUCACUUGAACCUGGGAGGCGGUGGUUGCAGUGAGCCGAGAUCGCACCAUUGCACUCCAGCCUGGGCAACAAGAGAAAAACUCUGUCUCAAAAAACAAAAAAUCUGUUAGGCUGCACACGGCGAUUCACUCCUGUAUUCCCAGUGCUUUGGGAGGCUGAGGUGAGAGGAUGCCUGAGGCCAGGAAUUCAGACCAGCCUGGGCAACAUAGUGAGACCCCAGCUCUAAAGAUUUGUUUUUGUUUUUUUUUUUUUUUUUUUUUUUUUUUUUUUUUUUUUUUUGAGACGGAGUCUCGCUCUGUCGCCCAGGCUAGAGUGCAGUGGUACCAUCUCCGCUCACUGCAACCUCCGCCUCCCGGGUUCCAGGGAUUCUCCUGCCUCAGCCUCCCUAGUAGCUGGAACUACAGGUGUGUGCUGCCAUGCCCAGCUAAUUUUUUUUUAUUUAAUAGAGACAAGAUUUCACCAUGUUGGCCAGGCUGGUCUCAAACUCCUGACCUCAGGUGAUCCACCCGCCUCAGCCUCCCAAAGUGCUGGGAUUACAGGUGUGAACCACCACACCUGGCCAACAAUAUUUGUUUUAAUUAGCCAGGCGUGGUAGCAUUUGUCCUAGCAAUUUGGGAGGUUGAGGUGGGAGAAUCACUUCAGCCCACUAGGUCGAGGCUGUAGUGAGCUAUAAUUGUACCACUGCACUCCAGCCUCGGGGACAGAGUGAGACCCUGUCUGCAAAUAAACAAAUAAAACAUCAGGCUGGGCUUGAGCAUCUAUUCCUGCUCAAAAUUUCGCAGGCUUCUCAGAAGAAAAUCCAAACCCCUUACAGUGACCCAGUUUGCCCUUGAGGCCUCCACCCACACCCCCUUCCCCCCAGUCUUAGGGGGUGGCCUGGCUGUUCCCUUCAACGGCAACGCUCUGCCUCCAUUGUUGGCCUCCUCUGCAGGGAGGGACUGUCUGAGCACCUGCCCGUGUCUGUGCAGCAUGGCACACUGACGUCAGGCCCACGUGCAUGCCCAGGUGGCCAGUCACACGCCAGGUGCUCCCUCAGUGUUGGCCAAGUGAGAGGAGCACACCUUCCGGGCGUUCAGACACCUCCCCGUGGCAGACACCGUUCGUUGCUACCAAACAGCCACCUCCUUCCUAAUGGGCUCCCAUUUUUCAGUGCUGGGCAAAGGUCCCUUGAUCUUGGAGUUGCAGCCUCUUUCUCUCCAAGGAGGGCGGUGACCAGCCUGAGCCAGUCAAUCCAGUGAUUGGUUCAGGAGUAGCCUGUGACCAGGAGUCCUGGUAGUGAACGACUGGGGCAGCCCUGGGGGUGAGGACCUUGCGCAGCCGUCACAGGCCCUGAUUGGACACUGGGCAGCUGCUAACCCAGUGUCUCCAGCUGCCUACCUGGAGAGCUCCAAGCGUAAGAAAAUAAACCCUGCCUGUUGAAGCCA